GCGCGCGCGCACACACACACACACACACAGAGAGAACAUCUCUAGUAAAAAGAAAAGUUGAGCUUUCUUAGCUAGAUGUGUGUAUUAGCCAGAAAAAGCCAAGGAGUGAAGGGUUUUAGAGAACUGGAGGAGAUAAAGUGGAGUCUGCAUAUGGGAGGCAUUUGAAAUGGACUUAAAUGUCUUUUUAAUGCUGACUUUUUCAGUUUUCUCCUUACCAGACACAUUGUUUUCAUGACAUUAGCCCCAGGCAUAGACACAUCAUUAAAAUGAACAUGUCAAAAAAUGAUUUCUGUUUAGAAAUAAGCAAAACAUUUUCAGUUGUGACCACCCAGGUGUAGAAUAAAGAACAGUGGAAUUGGGAGCCCUGAGUUCUAACAUAAACUUUCUUCAUGACAUAAGGCAAGUCUUCUAUGGCCUUUGGUUUCCUUACCUGUAAAACAGGAUGGCUCAAUGAAAUUAUCUUUCUUCUUUGCUAUAAUAGAGUAUCUCUGUGGGAAGAGGAAAAAAAAAGUCAAUUUAAAGGCUCCUUAUAGUUCCCCAACUGCUGUUUUAUUGUGCUAUUCAUGCCUAGACAUCACAUAGCUAGAAAGGCCCAUCAGACCCCUCAGGCCACUGCUGUUCCUGUCACACAUUCCUGCAAAGGACCAUGUUGCUAACUUGAAAAAAAUUACUAUUAAUUACACUUGCAGUUGUUGCUUAGUAACAUUUAUGAUUUUGUGUUUCUCGUGACAGCAUGAGCAGAGAUCAUUAAAAAUUAAACUUACAAAGCUGCUAAAGUGGGAAGAAGGAGAACUUGAAGCCACAAUUUUUGCACUUGCUUAGAAGCCAUCUAAUCUCAGGUUUAUAUGCUAGAUCUUGGGGGAAACACUGCAUGUCUCUGGUUUAUAUUAAACCACAUACAGCACACUACUGACACUGAUUUGUGUCUGGUGCAGCUGGAGUUUAUCACCAAGACAUAAAAAAACCUUGACCCUGCAGAAUGGCCUGGAAUUACAAUCAGAUGGGCCACAUGGCAUCCCGGUGAAAGAAAGCCCUAACCAGUUUUCUGUCUUGUUUCUGCUUUCUCCCUACAGUUCCACCAGGUGAGAAGAGUGAUGACCAUCCUUUUCCUUACUAUGGUUAUUUCAUACUUUGGUUGCAUGAAGGCUGCCCCCAUGAAAGAAGCAAACAUCCGAGGACAAGGUGGCUUGGCCUACCCAGGUGUGCGGACCCAUGGGACUCUGGAGAGCGUGAAUGGGCCCAAGGCAGGUUCAAGAGGCUUGACAUCAUUGGCUGACACUUUCGAACACGUGAUAGAAGAGCUGUUGGAUGAGGACCAGAAAGUUCGGCCCAAUGAAGAAAACAAUAAGGACGCAGACUUGUACACGUCCAGGGUGAUGCUCAGUAGUCAAGUGCCUUUGGAGCCUCCUCUUCUCUUUCUGCUGGAGGAAUACAAAAAUUACCUAGAUGCUGCAAACAUGUCCAUGAGGGUCCGGCGCCACUCUGACCCUGCCCGCCGAGGGGAGCUGAGCGUGUGUGACAGUAUUAGUGAGUGGGUAACGGCGGCAGACAAAAAGACUGCAGUGGACAUGUCGGGCGGGACGGUCACAGUCCUUGAAAAGGUCCCUGUAUCAAAAGGCCAACUGAAGCAAUACUUCUACGAGACCAAGUGCAAUCCCAUGGGUUACACAAAAGAAGGCUGCAGGGGCAUAGACAAAAGGCAUUGGAACUCCCAGUGCCGAACUACCCAGUCGUACGUGCGGGCCCUUACCAUGGAUAGCAAAAAGAGAAUUGGCUGGCGAUUCAUAAGGAUAGACACUUCUUGUGUAUGUACAUUGACCAUUAAAAGGGGAAGAUAGUGGAUUUAUGUUGUAUAGAUUAGAUUAUAUUGAGACAAAAAUUAUCUAUUUGUAUAUAUACAUAACAGGGUAAAUUAUUCAGUUAAGAAAAAAAUAAUUUUAUGAACUGCAUGUAUAAAUGAAGUUUAUACAGUACAGUGGUUCUACAAUCUAUUUAUUGGACAUGUCCAUGACCAGAAGGGAAACAGUCAUUUGCGCACAACUUAAAAAGUCUGCAUUACAUUCCUUGAUAAUGUUGUGGUUUGUUGCCGUUGCCAAGAACUGAAAACAUAAAAAGUUAAAAAAAAUAAUAAAUUGCAUGCUGCUUUAAUUGUGAAUUGAUAAUAAACUGUCCUCUUUCAGAAAACAGAAAAAAAACACACACACACACAACAAAAAUUUGAACCAAAACAUUCCGUUUACAUUUUAGACAGUAAGUAUCUUCGUUCUUGUUAGUACUAUAUCUGUUUUACUGCUUUUAACUUCUGAUAGCGUUGGAAUUAAAACAAUGUCAAGGUGCUGUUGUCAUUGCUUUACUGGCUUAGGGGAUGGGGGAUGGGGGGUAUAUUUUUGUUUGUUUUGUGUUUUUUUUUCGUUUGUUUGUUUUGUUUUUUAGUUCCCACAGGGAGUAGAGAUGGGGAAAGAAUUCCUACAAUAUAUAUUCUGGCUGAUAAAAGAUACAUUUGUAUGUUGUGAAGAUGUUUGCAAUAUCGAUCAGAUGACUAGAAAGUGAAUAAAAAUUAAGGCAACUGAACAAAAAAAUGCUCACACUCCACAUCCCGUGAUGCACCUCCCAGGCCCCGCUCAUUCUUUGGGCGUUGGUCAGAGUAAGCUGCUUUUGACGGAAGGACCUAUGUUUGCUCAGAACACAUUCUUUCCCCCCCUCCCCCUCUGGUCUCCUCUUUGUUUUGUUUUAAGGAAGAAAAAUCAGUUGCGCGUUCUGAAAUAUUUUACCACUGCUGUGAACAAGUGAACACAUUGUGUCACAUCAUGACACUCGUAUAAGCAUGGAGAACAGUGAUUUUUUUUUAGAACAGAAAACAACAAAAAAUAACCCCAAAAUGAAGAUUAUUUUUUAUGAGGAGUGAACAUUUGGGUAAAUCAUGGCUAAGCUUAAAAAAAACUCAUGGUGAGGCUUAACAAUGUCUUGUAAGCAAAAGGUAGAGCCCUGUAUCAACCCAGAAACACCUAGAUCAGAACAGGAAUCCACAUUGCCAGUGACAUGAGACUGAACAGCCAAAUGGAGGCUAUGUGGAGUUGGCAUUGCAUUUACCGGCAGUGCGGGAGGAAUUUCUGAGUGGCCAUCCCAAGGUCUAGGUGGAGGUGGGGCAUGGUAUUUGAGACAUUCCAAAACGAAGGCCUCUGAAGGACCCUUCAGAGGUGGCUCUGGAAUGACAUGUGUCAAGCUGCUUGGACCUCGUGCUUUAAGUGCCUACAUUAUCUAACUGUGCUCAAGAGGUUCUCGACUGGAGGACCACACUCAAGCCGACUUAUGCCCACCAUCCCACCUCUGGAUAAUUUUGCAUAAAAUUGGAUUAGCCUGGAGCAGGUUGGGAGCCAAAUGUGGCAUUUGUGAUCAUGAGAUUGAUGCAAUGAGAUAGAAGAUGUUUGCUACCUGAACACUUAUUGCUUUGAAACUAGACUUGAGGAAACCAGGGUUUAUCUUUUGAGAACUUUUGGUAAGGGAAAAGGGAACAGGAAAAGAAACCCCAAACUCAGGCCGAAUGAUCAAGGGGACCCAUAGGAAAUCUUGUCCAGAGACAAGACUUCGGGAAGGUGUCUGGACAUUCAGAACACCAAGACUUGAAGGUGCCUUGCUCAAUGGAAGAGGCCAGGACAGAGCUGACAAAAUUUUGCUCCCCAGUGAAGGCCACAGCAACCUUCUGCCCAUCCUGUCUGUUCAUGGAGAGGGUCCCUGCCUCACCUCUGCCAUUUUGGGUUAGGAGAAGUCAAGUUGGGAGCCUGAAAUAGUGGUUCUUGGAAAAAUGGAUCCCCAGUGAAAACUAGAGCUCUAAGCCCAUUCAGCCCAUUUCACACCUGAAAAUGUUAGUGAUCACCACUUGGACCAGCAUCCUUAAGUAUCAGAAAGCCCCAAGCAAUUGCUGCAUCUUAGUAGGGUGAGGGAUAAGCAAAAGAGGAUGUUCACCAUAACCCAGGAAUGAAGAUACCAUCAGCAAAGAAUUUCAAUUUGUUCAGUCUUUCAUUUAGAGCUAGUCUUUCACAGUACCAUCUGAAUACCUCUUUGAAAGAAGGAAGACUUUACGUAGUGUAGAUUUGUUUUGUGUUGUUUGAAAAUAUUAUCUUUGUAAUUAUUUUUAAUAUGUAAGGAAUGCUUGGAAUAUCUGCUGUAUGUCAACUUUAUGCAGCUUCCUUUUGAGGGACAAAUUUAAAACAAACAACCCCCCAUCACAAACUUAAAGGAUUGCAAGGGCCAGAUCUGUUAAGUGGUUUCAUAGGAGACACAUCCAGCAAUUGUGUGGUCAGUGGCUCUUUUACCCAAUAAGAUACAUCACAGUCACAUGCUUGAUGGUUUAUGUUGACCUAAGAUUUAUUUUGUUAAAAUCUCUCUCUGUUGUGUUCGUUCUUGUUCUGUUUUGUUUUGUUUUUUAAAGUCUUGCUGUGGUCUCUUUGUGGCAGAAGUGUUUCAUGCAUGGCAGCAGGCCUGUUGCUUUUUUAUGGCGAUUCCCAUUGAAAAUGUAAGUAAAUGUCUGUGGCCUUGUUCUCUCUAUGGUAAAGAUAUUAUUCACCAUGUAAAACAAAAAACAAUAUUUAUUGUAUUUUAGUAUAUUUAUAUAAUUAUGUUAUUGAAAAAAAUUGGCAUUAAAACUUAACCGCAUCAGAAGCCUAUUGUAAAUACAAGUUCUAUUUAAGUGUACUAAUUAACAUAUAAUAUAUGUUUUAAAUAUAGAAUUUUUAAUGUUUUUAAAUAUAUUUUCAAAGUACAUAAAA